CCGCAGACGCGCCAUCCUAGGGGUUGUGGGCCCAGGUUCCUGGCUUGAGGGGUCUUUGGGGUUAGUUUUGUGGGUGGGGCCCUCGGCUAUGAGGAGACCUUUGUGGUUAAGGCCCAUUCCCUUCUGAUGGCCAGGGGGCUCUGGCCCCAGCCACUGGUGUUCACAGAAAGGGAUAAUGGGGCAGAACUCAGGACCCCUCACCUCUUCUAGGGCAAGUUUGGGGUCUCAGGGGUCCUGGUGUCCCCAGGACUAGAGCUGGGUUUUGCUGAACACUGUGUCUUGGGAUCUUGGGUCCUAGAUACUAGAUUUUGGAAAUCUAUUUGUGCAUUCCUUUGUUUUGUAACUAAUUCUCAAUUAACUACUUAAUCAUUUUAUAAUUUCUUCAGGCACUCAUAAGUGUGUUCUAGAAUUUCCUAAUUCACGUGCUUAUUCCACAGUUUAAAUUAGGCAAAAAUUAGUGCAAAAAGUCCAAUCUGUUACGUAUCUAUUACUUCCACGAGAUGUCUGUACUCUCUCUAUAUUCACAGACCUGCCGCUGGGACACCUUGCUGGGAGUUUGGAACCUGUGAGUUUGGGAGUAGGGCUGUCCCAGCUGAGGAGCAGGGUCUUAGCUGAGCUUCUGGCCUUUUGGCAGGAGGCUGUUGGGUGUUCCCAUUGUUUUUGGGAGACUGCCCUGGCCUCUCAGUAAGAGGGUAAAUUUUGACAUUCAGCCCUAUGUCCCAGAGCCGGCACCCCAUCCCACAGCUAGGCCCAUCCUUCCAGCCCUCAAGCUUUUGCUGCUCCCCAGGAAGGCCCUUCCUGGUGCUGUUCCCUCCCCUCCUGCAGGUGCCUUUGGGGUCCUGCCUGGGCUGCAGCACCAGCUUGGCUUGAGGAAGGUCCCUGGUCUCCAGAAGCAGCAGUGACUGCUUAGGGAUGCUCACCCAGCAGCCGCUUUCUCUGGGCAGCCUUUGUGCUCCCAUAGGGGUGAGUCCUUUGAGACAGGGACCUGGGCCAUCCUCUCAGCUUCCCUGGGUCCAGGCCAGGGGGACACAUGGGUGGGGCACUUUCUGGCUCUUGGCGUUUGUGGGGGAGUCACGCAGGGAGUAGGGGAAUAUUCUUCUGUUCUGCAAGAAGGGGCUUGUAACCUCUUUUUAUAGGACUGGAAAACCUUGACACCCCCUAGUCCAUAAUUUGCAGCAGGUACUCCCAGGGCCUACCUGGCUCACAUUCCUCACCCCUACUGUUUCUCCACACGUUUGCAGUUCUGCAAGAAGGGAGGUGUUCUCUGUGUGUUUGGGGUCCAGCAACUGUGAGGGACCCAGCAGGCCGACACCUCCCAUCUGUUUCUGUCCCCAGGAUUCACGUGUUUUUCAAGGGCUAACGGAAAUGCUGAGAUCUAAAAGCAUGUUUAUUGCUGCCAAGGCCUGACGAUGAAACUUCAAGUCAAAUUAGUACCGUACAGAGUGGAUUUGCAGGGCAGUGGCAUGGAGCCCCUCUUCCCCGCGCCGUUCUGGGAGGUUAUCUACGGCAGCCACCUUCAGGGCAACCUGUCCCUCCUGAGCCCCAACCACAGUCUGCUGCCCCCGCAUCUGCUGCUCAAUGCCAGCCACGGCGCCUUCCUGCCCCUCGGGCUCAAGGUCACCAUCGUGGGGCUCUACCUGGCCGUGUGUGUCGGAGGGCUCCUGGGGAACUGCCUUGUCAUGUACGUCAUCCUCAGGCACACCAAAAUGAAGACAGCCACCAAUAUUUACAUCUUUAACCUGGCCCUGGCCGACACUCUGGUCCUGCUGACGCUGCCCUUCCAGGGCACGGACAUCCUCCUGGGCUUCUGGCCGUUUGGGAAUGCGCUGUGCAAGACAGUCAUUGCCAUUGACUACUACAACAUGUUCACCAGCACCUUCACCCUAACUGCCAUGAGUGUGGAUCGCUAUGUAGCCAUCUGCCACCCCAUCCGUGCCCUCGACGUCCGCACGUCCAGCAAAGCCCAGGCUGUCAAUGUGGCCAUCUGGGCCCUGGCCUCUGUUGUCGGUGUUCCCGUUGCCAUCAUGGGCUCGGCACAGGUCGAGGAUGAAGAGAUCGAGUGCCUGGUGGAGAUCCCUACCCCUCAGGAUUACUGGGGCCCGGUGUUUGCCAUCUGCAUCUUCCUCUUCUCCUUCAUCGUCCCCGUGCUCGUCAUCUCUGUCUGCUACAGCCUCAUGAUCCGGCGGCUCCGUGGAGUCCGCCUGCUCUCGGGCUCCCGAGAGAAGGACCGGAACCUGCGGCGCAUCACUCGGCUGGUGCUGGUGGUAGUGGCUGUGUUCGUGGGCUGCUGGACGCCUGUCCAGGUCUUCGUGCUGGCCCAAGGGCUGGGGGUUCAGCCGAGCAGCGAGACUGCCGUGGCCAUUCUGCGCUUCUGCACGGCCCUGGGCUACGUCAACAGCUGCCUCAACCCCAUCCUCUACGCCUUCCUGGAUGAGAACUUCAAGGCCUGCUUCCGCAAGUUCUGCUGUGCAUCUGCCCUGCGCCGGGACGUGCAGGUGUCUGACCGCGUGCGCAGCAUUGCCAAGGACGUGGCCCUGGCCUGCAAGACCUCUGAGACGGUACCGCGGCCCGCAUGACUAGGCGUGGACCUGCCCAUGGUGCCUGUCAGCCCGCAGAGCCCAUCUACGCCCAACACAGAGCUCACACAGGUCACUGCUCUCUAGGCGGACACACCCUGGGCCCUGAGCAUCCAGAGCCUGGGAUGGGCUUUUCCCUGUGGGCCAGGGAUGCUCGGUCCCAGAGGAGGACCUAGUGACAUCAUGGGACAGGUCAAAGCAUUAGGGCCACCUCCAUGGCCCCAGACAGACUAAAGCUGCCCUCCUGGUGCAGGGCCGAGGGGACACAAGGACCUACCUGGAAGCAGCUGACAUGCUGGUGGACGGCCGUGACUGGAGCCCGUGCCCCUCCCUCCCCGUGCUUCAUGUGACUCUUGGCCUCUCUGCUGCUGCGUUGGCAGAACCCUGGGUGGGCAGGCACCCGGAGGAGGAGCAGCAGCUGUGUCAUCCUGUGCCCCCCAUGUGCUGUGUGCUGUUUGCAUGGCAGGGCUCCAGCUGCCUUCAGCCCUGUGACGUCUCCUCAGGGCAGCUGGACAGGCUUGGCACUGCCCGGGAAGUGCAGCAGGCAGCUUUUCUUUGGGGUGGGACUUGCCCUGAGCUUGGAGCUGCCACCUGGAGGACUUGCCUGUUCCGACUCCACCUGUGCAGCCGGGGCCACCCCAGGAGAAAGUGUCCAGGUGGGGGCUGGCAGUCCCUGGCUGCAGACCCCGAGCUGGCCCUGGGCCAGCCGCACCUCUGAAGGUUUUCUGUGUGCUGCACGGUGCAGGCCUCAUCCCUGACUGCAGCUUGACUCUGGGCCCAACCCCCAUUUCCCUUCAGGAGACCAGCGAGAGGCCCUGGCCCAUUCCCUCCAGCGGUGCAAUGAACUAUCAUGCUGUGGACCGUCAACCCAGCCCUGCUUCUCAGUGUGGGGCAGGUGUCUCAGGACGAAGGCGCCGCGUGACCACAUGGGCAGCUCUGUUCACAAAGUGGAGGCCUCGUUUUCCUGGUCUUGACUGCUCUGUUUGGGUGGGAGAAGAUUCUCUGGGGGUCCCCACAUCCUCCCAAGGCUCCCCUCACAGCCUCUCCUUUGCUUGAAGCCAGAGGUCAGUGGCCGUGCUGUGUUGCGGGGGAAGCUGUGUGGAAGGAGAAGCUGGUGGCCACAGCAGAGUCCUGCUCUGGGGACGCCUGCUUCAUUUACAAGCCUCAAGAUGGCUCUGUGUAGGGCCUGAGCUUGCUGCCCAACGGGAGGAUGGCUUCACAGCAGAGCCAGCAUGAGGGGUGGGGCCUGGCAGGGCUUGCUUGAGCCAAACUGCAAAGGCUGUGGUGGCUGUGAGGACACUGCGGGGGUUGGGGGGGGGGCGUCUGUACCUCAGGGGAUGCCCCGCUGUGGUCACCCAGAGAAUCACCCUUCCUGGUCUACAGAUGGAAGCUGCAGGUUGGUGACUUUGCAAAUGCACUUCCUACAGAUGAACUAUUAAAAGACCUGCAACAUUGAAAAAACUCAUUUUUUCCACCAAAACCUUGGCCAGGUAACCUACCUUAGGCACCUGCAAAGAACAGGAAGUGAUGGCUGUCUCGCAACAGAGCCUGGGCUGCUCCUCCUGCUCUGGGGAGUCUAGGCCGUGGGGACUGUUCUGGGGAGGCUCAUGCUGUCUCCAUGACGUCUGUGGCAGGAGUCCCUGAGGACGGGAGCUGCCUAGCUACAGUUUUCUUGCCAAGGCGAGGUGUUUUGUGAAUCUGUGCUGAUGUAAUGUGCACCUUCACGUAUUUAUGCAUGUGGCAAGCGUUACUUCCUGUGCACGUAGCCAGCCCUGGGUCUGUCUCUGGGGUAAUGAAAAAGGACCCUAAUAAACACCUGCUCACUGGCUGGGUAUUCUUUGUAA